GCCGGUGGAACCUAGAGCCCCGCGGAAGAGCAGAACGUUUGGGAGUGUGCAGCUCCUGGGCCCGGCUCAGGCCCGUCGCGGAGGCGCGGCGCAGGGGAGCGCUCGGGUGGGAGUCUCGCUCCUCCACCAGUUUAUUGCGACGUAGCAUCCAGGCCUAGGCCUCCCCGUCCAUCCCCGCCGGACUCGGGCCUCUGGCAGCAGCGGGUGACGCAGACGGAACAUCAUGUCGUCCGCGGCCGAGCCUCCGCCACCCCCGCCUCCCGAGAGCGCGCCUUCCAAGCCCGCAGCCUCGAUCGCCAGCGGCGGGAGCAACAGCAGCAACAAAGGCGGCCCCGAAGGCGUCGCGGCGCAGGCGGUUGCGUCUGCGGCCAGCGCUGGUCCCGCAGACGCCGAGAUGGAGGAAAUAUUUGAUGAUGCGUCACCUGGAAAGCAAAAGGAAAUCCAAGAACCAGAUCCUACCUAUGAAGAAAAAAUGCAAACUGACCGGGCAAAUAGAUUCGAGUAUUUAUUAAAGCAGACAGAACUUUUUGCACAUUUCAUUCAACCUGCUGCUCAGAAGACUCCAACUUCACCUUUGAAGAUGAAACCAGGGCGCCCACGAAUAAAAAAAGAUGAGAAGCAGAACUUACUAUCCGUUGGCGAUUACCGACACCGUAGAACAGAGCAAGAGGAGGAUGAAGAGCUAUUAACAGAAAGCUCCAAAGCAACCAAUGUUUGCACUCGAUUUGAAGACUCUCCAUCGUAUGUAAAAUGGGGUAAACUGAGAGAUUAUCAGGUCCGAGGAUUAAACUGGCUCAUUUCUUUGUAUGAGAAUGGCAUCAAUGGUAUCCUUGCAGAUGAAAUGGGCCUAGGAAAGACUCUUCAAACAAUUUCUCUUCUUGGGUACAUGAAACAUUAUAGAAACAUUCCUGGGCCUCAUAUGGUUUUGGUUCCUAAGUCUACAUUACACAACUGGAUGAGUGAAUUCAAGAGAUGGGUACCAACACUUAGAUCUGUUUGUUUGAUAGGAGAUAAAGAACAAAGAGCUGCUUUUGUCAGAGACGUUUUAUUACCGGGAGAAUGGGAUGUAUGUGUAACAUCUUAUGAAAUGCUUAUUAAAGAGAAGUCUGUGUUCAAAAAAUUUAAUUGGAGAUACUUAGUAAUAGAUGAAGCUCACAGGAUCAAAAAUGAAAAAUCUAAGUUGUCAGAAAUAGUGAGGGAAUUCAAGACUACAAAUAGACUAUUAUUAACUGGAACACCUCUUCAGAACAACUUGCAUGAGCUGUGGUCACUUCUUAACUUUCUGUUGCCAGAUGUGUUUAAUUCAGCAGAUGACUUUGAUUCCUGGUUUGAUACAAACAACUGCCUUGGGGAUCAAAAACUAGUUGAGAGGCUUCAUAUGGUUUUGCGUCCAUUCCUCCUUCGUCGAAUUAAGGCUGAUGUUGAAAAGAGUUUGCCUCCAAAGAAGGAAGUAAAAAUCUAUGUGGGCCUCAGCAAAAUGCAAAGGGAAUGGUAUACUCGGAUAUUAAUGAAGGAUAUAGAUAUACUCAACUCAGCAGGCAAGAUGGACAAAAUGAGGUUAUUGAACAUCCUAAUGCAGUUGAGAAAAUGUUGUAAUCAUCCAUAUCUCUUUGAUGGAGCAGAACCUGGUCCACCUUAUACAACAGAUAUGCAUCUAGUAACCAACAGUGGCAAAAUGGUGGUUUUAGACAAGCUGCUCCCUAAGUUAAAAGAACAAGGUUCACGAGUACUAAUCUUCAGUCAAAUGACAAGGGUAUUGGACAUUUUGGAAGAUUAUUGCAUGUGGAGAAAUUAUGAGUACUGCAGGUUGGAUGGUCAGACACCCCAUGAUGAGAGACAAGACUCCAUCAAUGCAUACAAUGAACCAAACAGCACAAAGUUUGUUUUCAUGUUAAGCACGCGUGCUGGUGGUCUUGGCAUCAAUCUUGCGACUGCUGAUGUAGUAAUUUUGUAUGAUUCUGAUUGGAAUCCCCAAGUAGAUCUUCAGGCUAUGGACCGAGCACAUAGAAUUGGGCAGACUAAGACAGUCAGAGUGUUCCGCUUUAUAACUGAUAACACUGUAGAAGAAAGAAUAGUAGAACGUGCUGAGAUGAAACUCAGACUGGAUUCAAUAGUCAUUCAACAAGGGAGGCUUGUGGAUCAGAAUCUGAACAAAAUUGGGAAAGAUGAAAUGCUUCAAAUGAUUAGACAUGGAGCAACACAUGUGUUUGCUUCAAAGGAAAGUGAGAUCACUGAUGAAGAUAUCGAUGGUAUUUUGGAAAGAGGUGCAAAGAAGACUGCAGAGAUGAAUGAAAAGCUCUCCAAGAUGGGCGAAAGUUCACUUAGAAACUUUACAAUGGAUACAGAGUCAAGUGUUUAUAACUUCGAAGGAGAAGACUAUAGAGAAAAACAAAAGAUUGCAUUCACAGAGUGGAUUGAACCACCUAAACGAGAAAGAAAAGCCAACUAUGCCGUUGAUGCAUAUUUCAGGGAAGCUCUUCGUGUUAGUGAACCUAAAGCACCCAAGGCUCCUCGACCUCCAAAACAACCCAAUGUUCAGGAUUUCCAGUUCUUUCCUCCACGUUUAUUUGAAUUACUGGAAAAAGAAAUUCUGUUUUACAGAAAAACUAUUGGGUACAAGGUACCUCGAAAUCCUGAGCUGCCUAAUGCAGCACAGGCACAAAAAGAAGAACAGCUUAAAAUUGAUGAAGCUGAAUCCCUUAAUGAUGAAGAGUUAGAGGAAAAAGAGAAGCUUCUAACACAGGGAUUUACCAAUUGGAAUAAGAGAGAUUUUAACCAGUUUAUCAAAGCUAAUGAGAAGUGGGGUCGUGAUGAUAUUGAAAAUAUAGCAAGAGAAGUAGAAGGCAAAACUCCAGAAGAAGUCAUUGAAUAUUCAGCUGUGUUUUGGGAAAGGUGCAACGAGCUCCAGGACAUAGAGAAGAUUAUGGCUCAGAUUGAAAGGGGAGAGGCGAGAAUUCAAAGAAGAAUAAGCAUCAAGAAAGCACUUGACACAAAGAUUGGACGGUACAAAGCACCUUUUCAUCAGCUGAGAAUAUCAUAUGGUACUAACAAAGGAAAAAACUAUACUGAAGAAGAAGAUCGUUUUCUGAUUUGUAUGCUUCACAAACUUGGAUUUGACAAAGAAAAUGUUUAUGAUGAAUUGCGACAGUGUAUUCGCAACUCUCCUCAGUUCAGAUUUGACUGGUUUCUUAAGUCCAGAACUGCAAUGGAGCUCCAGAGGAGAUGUAAUACCUUAAUUACUUUGAUUGAAAGAGAAAACAUGGAACUAGAAGAAAAGGAGAAGGCAGAGAAAAAGAAACGAGGACCAAAGCCUUCAACACAGAAACGUAAAAUGGAUGGCGCACCUGAUGGUCGAGGAAGAAAAAAGAAGCUGAAACUAUGAAUAUGUUUUUGUUUCAUAAUCACUAACUUUAAACCAGUAGUUCUUUAAUUUACGGGUCUUCAUAAGAUGUACUGUACAAUGCUCAAUUGUUAUGUCAUUUAAAGACAUCAGGUUCAUCUGUUUACUGAGCUAGAAACAUAGUAUGUAGUUUCACUUUUUUAAAUGCAACAGCUGUGCUGAAAUUUUUUUAUCAUUAACACUUGAAGUAAUAAAAUAGGCUUCAUUUAUUACUAAGUGUUUCAUUUGAUUUAUUUUUCUAUUGUAGUUCCAUUUGUGAAGAUUGUGACUUUUUGUUUAUUAGCUAUAAUUUCUACACUUGUAAGGCUUAAAAACAAGUUAAAAAGAAAAUUGCAAAUAACAUUUGUCCCUUUCAGUCUUCACCUAGUUGUGUAAUUAUUUUAAUUCACUUUGCCUUUGCAGAAAUUUGGGUAUUUUCUUUGUAGUGCUAUUGAGUCUCAUCUGGAAAGAUUAUAUAAAUUGCAUUCUCCUUGCUUAUGUGGGUAGAAUGGGAAAAGAAGGCAAGACAAAGUAUACUUAAAUUCUAUGCAUAUUUCUGUUAUGCUUUCUGUUUUUUUUAGUUGAUUCUGAAAUGAAUAUGCCCUAUUCUUUUGAAAGAAUGGCCUUUUAGUUGUAUAGCCAAAGACAUUUAGUAUUUUCCGGUUCCUUAAGGUAUUACUGUACCAUUUUGUAAAAGGAAUAUUAUUAUUAUUAUUUUUAAUUAUUUGGUAAAUAUUUUGUCAUAUGACCUUCUGAAGCAGCCACAACUUAGAUAAUGUCAGAACUAAGGUGAUUUUUUUUUUUUAAUUUUGAAAGCCCAGCCAAAAUGAGGUGUGAAUUUGUCAUACUGUUACAUUGAAAUUGGUAACAAAAUAUAUCCCCUCCCAUUUGGACUUUUAGGGUAAAUGAAAAUUUUAUUGUAUUUUAAAGUAGUUUCUAAGUGUUAGCAAGACUGACUAUAAUUCCAGUUUCUGUUUUCUAUGGACAGACCUGAUAAACUGGAGACCCUAAAGCAGGAAUACCCAAAUUAUAGUGUCAGGAUUUUAGCUGUACCAGAGGCCUUUAUGUGCUACACAUAAUUUGUAUAAAAUUUUAUAUGUGCAGAUUGGGUACAUAAACAGUUCUCCAUUUUUCUAAGGGAAUGCAAUAAAUGUAGCAUCGUGAAUAAAUAUAACUUUUAUAAUCCGUAAAGUGGUCUUUUCUUUCCAUUUCUUUAAUUGUUUUCUCAAUUUUUAUUCACUUUUUCCUUUAGGACACAUUUCCCUUAAUUGGAUAUCUUUCCCUUAAAUUUCUAUUAGUAGUUGUUUUCAUCUGCCCACAUGUAAUUGAAGAUUUAAAAAAAAAAUUUUGAUACCUGCAGUAUUACUAAUACUGCUUAAUUUCUUGAAAUGUGGAAUUGCUGCUGUUAAUGUCAAGCAAAACGCAGUAUUUAUGGCAAAUUGUAAAGUAAUUUGAAUUUAGUGCUACCUCAAAAUUAACUUUUUAAAUACUAUGUUAGAUUCUUAACAGUUAAAGGUCUAAUACAUGCAUGAGGAAUGGUUACUUAUGAAAGGAAAAAGAAUUUGUAAGAGUUAUCACCUCAGUUUGGAAGAAAUUGAAAAAAUGUAAGGCUGAAGAAAACUUACGGAGGUCACAAAAGUGAUGUUUUCAAGAGGAGGAGAAACUGGGAGGGAGAUACACAGUGGAAAUGCAAAAUGAAUCAAGUAUAGUGGUAGCCCUGAGAGCUUAGGGACUCAAAUGGAAACUGUGUGAAGGGAAACUCACUUGAAAAAAAAGCAUGAACCAGCUAGGCCCUGCCACCACUGUGUUUGGCCAAGUUCACAAAUCUGUUUUAACCUGUCACUUCCCUGUCACUUCUCUGGCUUUCCUCUCCCGCUAAGCUUUUGUUUCCUGGCAGUAAUUAAAAUCUUCUGUCAGUGCCACAGCUACUACUGCUACUGGAACUGCCUUAACCACUACUGCUACUGGAACUGCCUUAGCCACCUUGGUAUCGUGGUUUGGCAAAGUAUUGGCCUCUACCACCAUAGGGCCCAGAGCUUCUGCCUCCAAAGUUUCCUCCCUUCAUGGGUCCAAAAUUUGAAGACUGAUUGUUGUCAUUGCCAAAAUCAUUGUAGCUUUUACCACCUCCAAAAUUGCUUCAAUCAUUACCAAAUCUAUUAUAGCAAUCCCCACUGCCACCAUAUCCAUCACCACCACCAUGGCUGCCACCAAAGCCACCACGAUCACAGAACUUGAUGACUGUAUUUGUGACUAAUUGUAUAAUAGUUUCUGUUCUGUGGAAAGUAAAGCAUUCCAACACAGGGUUUCAGUGUAGAUUGUUUUGUUUUGUACCCAUGCUGUUGAUUGCUAAAUGUUUUAAUAAUCUGAUCAUGAUACUGAAUAAAUGUCUUUUUUUUUUUUUAACAACAAAGCAUGAAAGAUUGCUUAAUUGUACAUCUGACAAAGUGCUGGAGGCUAUUAUAAAGUGUAAUUAUUACUACUUUUAAGAGACAGGGUCUUGCUCUGUCACCCAGGCUGGAGUGCAGUGGUGCAAUCACAGCUCACUGCAACCUCAAACUUCAGGGCUCAAGUGAUCCUCCCACCUCAGCUUCCCAAGUAGCUAGGACUACAGAUACCACGCCCAGCUAAGUUUUUUUAGUUUUUGUAGAGAUAGGGCCUUGCUAUGUUGCCCAGUCCGGUCUCAAACGCCGACUUCAGGCAAUCCUCUUGCGUCAACCUCUCAAAGUGCUGGGAUUACAUGUGUAAGCCUACAUUCCAAAGUGCUGGGAUCAUAGUUGUGAGCCUACACCACACCUGGCCUACAUUUUGUUUUUCAUAAAGUUGAGAGAAGCAAAUCCUAAGCAUAGAGUACAAGUUGAGCAUCCCUAAUCAAAAAAUCUAAAAUCAGAAAUGCUCCAUAAUUUGAAUGCUCAUUAGGGCAUUUCUGAUUUUUGGAUUAGGGAUGCUGAACUGAUAAGUAUAAUGCAAGUAUUCUAAAGUCUGGAAAAUGCUAAAAACACUUCUGGUUCCAGGCAUUUCAGAUAAGGAUUGCUCCAUCUGCCCUUUGAGUAUUUAAUAUAUGCCGAUUGUUUGAACUAAUCUGGAUUUAAUUAUAUAAAUGAUUAUAUAAAUGAUCUUUGGCUUAGUACCUUUCUUAAUCUCGAUCUUAAAAAGCAUUGUAAAACACCCCUGUGGUUUUUCAGAAAAAUUCUGAGUAAAAAAUAAAUUUCAUCUUGUUCUAUCCCUUUGAAUCUAAAAAACAAAUCUUUUUGAAAGGAUGUGCUACUAUAUUUCAAACCAGUAGUUUUGGAGUAGAACAUUGCUAAAAAAAUGGGUACUAAGGAGGGUAAUUUAAACAAAGUAGAUUAAUGACACAAGGUGGAUUGAUGAACUCAUAAAUCCAAAUGAAUGGAAUGCUAGAAGACAUGUAUUAACGGAGUAGCUGUUACCAAAAUAUAUACAUAUUUUGUAUAUGUACAUAGCUGUUACCAAAAUGUAUCUUUGCCUGUUGGAAUCUGAUGUCAAGAUCAAAGGUGAGGGCAUCCCUCAGAUGACAGAUAAUGGGCAAAAUACAUUCUUGGUGUGGAGCAGUGCUGCAGAAUUAACUUCGCUGUGUACAUCCCAGAAUCGUUUUGGAUCUGUUAAGGUUUUUAUUAGAAUGAUUAAAUAGGCUUUUGCAGCAUUAACUUUACAGUAGUUACCAGAAAAGACUAUGCUACAAGAACCAAAAUUGAAGUAAGAAGAAAAAGACUGAAAUGAUAUGAUUCUAAAUGAAAAAAAUGAAGAAGUGGAAUAGUUUCUCCACAGGCAUAAGAGGCAAAGCAUUGUUUCAGAAGUGGACUGGCACCUCACCUGAGAUACUCAAGACUGGCAACAUGGGUCUACAUUCUUUGUUACCACAGAUUCCCUUGUGUCCGGAGAGAUUCCCUAGCUCUAAUGACAGCUUUUUUGGGGGGUAAUGAGGCUAUGAGAAGAUUGAGGAUCUAGGUACUUGCCUUUAACUCUACAGCAUACAAGGUGUGUGGCUCUUAUCUCUAGGACACCAAUAUUUAAUGUUGCAUAUCAUGUAUCUCCAGUACAAGAAGAAAGUUUAUCAGAAUUUAGUUAAUGUUGGAAACUUUGUAAUAUAAACAAUGUAAACACUACAUUGACAAAAAUAUUUUAUUAAUACAAAGAAUAUGCAUAUAGUUUGCUUACUACAGAAAUUCUUGUUUUUGAUGUAGACAACCCAAAGGAGUUUUUAUGUAUAUAGAUUGUGAAUAAAUUGGGAAAAGAAAUAGAGAUAAGUAGAGAUUAUUUCACUUCAUUAAACUUUUGAAGUCCUAA